AGCUAGAGCUCUAGCUUCACAAUAAAAUGUGUGCAAAUACUCUCCACAGAGAUAAGUCCCCACCUCAGUCGGUAUAGAAAAGCAUGAUAAAGGUUGGAAAAAAUGGAUAAAAAUGUUGAAAGAACCUCCAGUUCCUUAUUAGGCGAAGAUACAAUAUUUAUUCCUUGUCUCCUGGGAUAAAUCUCUUCUGCCUAUUGUCCUCCCAGUUCUCAGUGCUGAUGCUUAAUUUUCAAAACUUCUAUAUUACCAAGGGACCUACGACAUCAGCCAAAGAAAUACUCAGCAAGUACAAAAUCUGUUCCAGGGAGCUGCUUUUGUGCAGAGGGAAAAUUUUGUUCCUACAGGUUUUUAAGUGGGUACGAGGCAAGGAGCUAUCUGAUCCGGGCAAAACCAUUACAAUUUAGAUAUCUACCUAUAGAACAUUUUUUUUUUCCUUUAAAAAUUGGAAAAUACAAGAAGUUUGGAUUUUUUUUUCCCGAUUCUUUUUUUGGAGGGGGAAAUUGCAUCGUAAGCUUUCGGAGAAACCCAACAUGUCAACUACCUUUCCGGGACUAGUCCACGAUGCCGAGAUACGUCACGACGGAUCAAACAGCUACCGUUUGAUGCAGCUUGGCUGUCUGGAGUCAGUAGCCAAUUCCACUGUCGCCUAUUCCUCCUCCUCUCCUUUAACUUACUCCACCACCGGCACCGAGUUUGCGUCCCCCUACUUCUCCACUAACCACCAGUACACCCCGCUCCACCACCAGUCCUUCCAUUACGAGUUUCAGCACAGCCACCCGGCCGUCACCCCCGACGCCUACUCUCUGAACUCUCUCCACCACUCGCAACAGUACUACCAGCAGAUCCACCACGGGGAGCCCACCGACUUUAUUAACCUGCACAAUGCGCGGGCGCUCAAGUCGUCCUGCCUGGACGAGCAGAGGCGGGAGCUGGGCUGCCUCGAUGCCUACCGCCGCCAUGACCUGUCCCUCAUGAGCCAUGGCUCUCAGUAUGGAAUGCACCCAGAUCAAAGACUCCUGCCAGGGCCCAGCCUGGGGCUGGCCGCCGCGGGAGCAGACGACUUGCAGGGCUCUGUGGAGGCCCAGUGUGGGCUUGUUCUCAAUGGCCAAGGUGGAGUGAUAAGAAGAGGUGGCACCUGUGUGGUCAACCCCACAGACUUAUUUUGCUCUGUCCCUGGCCGUUUGUCCCUUCUUAGUUCUACUUCCAAAUACAAGGUGACCAUUGCUGAGGUAAAGAGGCGCCUCUCCCCACCUGAGUGCCUCAAUGCUUCACUCUUGGGAGGCAUUUUGAGAAGAGCAAAAUCAAAGAAUGGGGGCCGCUGCCUGAGAGAGAAAUUGGAUAGGCUUGGCUUAAACUUACCAGCAGGAAGACGGAAAGCAGCUAAUGUCACCCUCCUUACUUCCUUGGUUGAAGGGGAGGCUUUGCACUUGGCUCGGGAUUUUGGCUACACUUGUGAAACAGAGUUUCCAGCCAAAGCAGUAGGAGAACAUCUUGCCAGACAACAUAUGGAACAGAAAGAACAGACAGCAAGAAAAAAGAUGAUCCUGGCGACCAAACAAAUCUGUAAAGAAUUCCAAGACCUCUUGAGCCAAGAUAGAUCACCACUGGGAUCCUCCAGACCCACUCCAAUUCUAGACCUUGACAUCCAGAGACAUUUAACACAUUUCAGUUUGAUCACUCAUGGCUUUGGGACUCCGGCAAUAUGUGCAGCUCUAAGCACUUUCCAAACAGUUCUCAGUGAAAUGCUGAACUACUUGGAAAAACACACUACUCACAAGAACGGCGGAGCGGCGGAUUCUGGCCAAGGACAUGCCAACUCGGAGAAAGCUCCCCUGCGGAAAACUUCAGAGGCUGCCGUGAAAGAGGGCAAAACAGAAAAGACAGACUAGCUACAUCAAACAGAAUCUAUUUCCAGAGAGUCUUGCUGCUGAUAUUUUUUCUAAUAUAUAUAUCAUUGAGGGUGACUAAUCUUCAGUGGACCAAAUCUCUACCCUUCCCCAACCCUCCAUAAAAAAACAAAAAUGGAAAUGAAAAAUGAAACAAAAAAGGACAAAACCA